GUGACUUGCUCCUCCUUGUCUUCCACCACGAUUGUGAGGCCUCCCUAGCCACGUGGAGCUCUCAAAGGUGGAGACAACCCAAAUGUCCUUCAAUGGAUGGUUAAAUAUACCAUGGUACAUCUAUACCAUAGAUUACUACUCAGCAAUAAAAAGGACAAACUAUUGAUACAAGCAACCACUUGGGUGAAUCUCCAGGGAAUUGUGCCAAGUGGAAAGAGCCAAGCCCAAAUGAUUAUACACUAUAUGAUUCCAGAACCCACAGAGCCGCAUUUCCCUUGGUUUCGGAGGACACGCGAAAAAUAACAACAGCAAAGGGUUCUCGAGCAUCUCCUUCGCGCCAGACGGUGUGUUGUACUUUGUCAUCGUCGCAGUAAGGCCGGUGCUAUCGCCCUCCUAGUUUGACCAAGCGAGAGGACUUUCUCCAGAUGGGCCCCUCCCGAGAGAAUGGUCGCCGUCCCGCUCUCCUGUUCGGGUCACCACCGGCCGGGCGCCACUCGAACGAGCCCCGGCCAGCCGUCACCCUAAUCAUUCCCGAAGGAGGGGCCAUCAGAGCUACAGCUCAUCAGGGUCAAUCAGAAGGGGCGCCCGCACGCAAAGGUCACCUGCAAACCGAAGCGGCGCACGGAUAAGGUCCGGGACUUGAAGUCUAUCUCCAAACAUUCAGGCUCCUCCUCCGACUCCUCCUCGAACUGGCGCUCAGAGGCGCCACCAUUCGGAAGGAGCCCAGGCCACGCGCAGCUCGCCCUCCCGCACCGCGAGGGCAGCAGCCGCCUCAUGCGACUCGAGAACGCUAGAGGGCGCCGCUUCCGGGAGCCCGCAAGCGGCUUCCGGGUGCUCGCGCGCCGACCUGGACGCAGAGAAGCCAGAGACUUUCGCUUCCGGCUGCCGCAGGCGCUUCGCUGGUGCAGGUAAGCUCCGCACACUCUCGGCCGGUCCCGAGUCCGACUCCCUCAAGGGUGACGCGAGCUCUGCCCUUUAACCGGAAACGUCUCCCUGCUCACCCCACCCCCGCGCAGACGCAGUGCUGAGCACACAGCUACCGGACAAAGAGUGACGCCCGGAGCUGGAGUUAUGGCGGCUACGGAGCCGAUCUUGGCGGCCACUGGGAGUCCCGCGGCGGUGCCACCGGAGAAACUGGAAGGAGCCGGUUCGAGCUCAGCCCCUGAGCGUAACUGUGUGGGCUCCUCGCUGCCAGAGGCCUCACCGCCUGCCCCUGAGCCUUCCAGUCCCAACGCCGCGGUCCCUGAAGCCAUCCCUACGCCCCGAGCUGCGGCCUCCGCGGCCCUGGAGCUGCCUCUCGGGCCCGCACCCGUGAGCGUAGCGCCUCAGGCCGAAGCUGAAGCGCGCUCCACACCAGGCCCCGCCGGCUCUAGACUCGGUCCCGAGACGUUCCGCCAGCGUUUCCGGCAGUUCCGCUACCAGGAUGCGGCGGGUCCCCGGGAGGCUUUCCGGCAGCUGCGGGAGCUGUCCCGCCAGUGGCUGCGGCCUGACAUCCGCACCAAGGAGCAGAUCGUGGAGAUGCUGGUGCAAGAGCAGCUGCUCGCCAUCCUGCCCGAGGCGGCUCGGGCCCGGCGGAUCCGCCGCCGCACGGAUGUGCGCAUCACUGGCUGAGCGGUGGAGCUGCGGGCGGCCAGGGCCGGGCGCUCUGUGCGGACUGGGGCCAUGAUCGGGCCCGGGGGCCUGAGCCUGGGACCCCACCCCGUGUUAAUGAAAAAUGAGUUUUGGCAGCGCC